GUUGUUAAGCAUAGGACCUAAGAAGAGGUGGCAGUCUCUUUCCUCUCCGCACUUGGCAGGCCACCCACUCAUUCCUGAUAAUCACAUUUAAGAGAGCUCUGGACAAGCUGGAAUGCAUCCAAGAGAAUCCCUCAACAUGCUGGUGAGUGGGAUUGUGACCAGGUCAUAUCAGGAGUAGCCUAAGGGACAGGUAAUGUGUGUCUUGGAUGAAUUGGAGUCAGACUUAAGAGUCCCCAGGGCAGAAACAAAAUCCAGUGAGGGAGAGAUGCAGGGAGCUGGAUUUUAGCUCCUAAGGUAGAAAAUUUCCAAAAGGCUGAUCAAAGAUUAAAUGGCUGCCUUAAAAGGUAAUGAGUUCCUUGUUAGUGGAGGUGUUCAACCACUGCUUGGUGGGAAGACACUGUAAGGAGGAUUCAGGCAAGUGGGAAGGGGGCUUUUUCCAGUCCCUGAAAUCAAUGAUUCUAACAGGAAAAGAUGCUCCGGGGUGCGGUGAGCGCUUACCUCUGCUCUUGCAGAGACACUGACAGACGUUCAUUCAACAUCUGUUCCUGCCAGGCACUGUGCGCGCUGAACACAGAAGUACAGCCUCUAUGAAGCAGCCGCUGUAGGCCUCAGAGACAGCUGAUAGAUGUAACACUGUUGUCUCCAUGUUUCAAACUUCGGUCAUGGUCUUACUAGGUCUCCUCAUUAAGGGGACUCACUAUGUGUCCAGUAACGCUUUCUUGUUACCAGAUGACAGAGAGUCAGGCUGUCAGAGUUCACGACUUUAGGUGCACAGUUUCACCCUGUCUGGUCCUUGGGAGACGGAGAAGGGGUCAGGAGAAAACGUGGGUGAAGAGGCAGCAAAGCCGCAGGAGAUAUGAACUAAUUGCUCAACGUGGGUGUAGCACGGAUUAGGCCUUUUACAGCAAGCGCUGCCAGCAGGGAACUGGUGGAUGUACUCUUGACCACGCUCGGCUGGACUCUGGGGAGCCCAAGACGGGUGGCUUUCUAGAAGAUGACCAUAGAGGACCUUCCAGAUUUUCCAUUAGAAGGAAAUCCUUUGUUUGGAAGAUACCCAUUUAUAUUUUCUGCUUCUGAUACCCCAGUUAUCUUUUCCAUUUCUGCAGCACCAAUGCCUUCAGACUGUGAAUUUUCUUUCUUUGAUCCUAAUGAUGCAUCAUGCCAGGAAAUUCUUUUUGAUCCCAAAACUUCAGUUUCAGAAUUAUUUGCCAUUUUGAGACAGUGGGUUCCUCAGGUCCAACAAAACAUUGACAUUAUUGGAAAUGAGAUUCUUAAGAGAGGUUGCAAUGUGAAUGAUAGAGAUGGAUUGACAGAUAUGACUCUUUUACAUUAUACCUGCAAAUCUGGAGCUCAUGGUAUUGGUGAUGUGGAAACAGCUGUAAAAUUUGCAACUCAGCUUAUUGACCUGGGAGCAGACAUUAGUUUGCGGAGUCGCUGGACAAACAUGAAUGCUUUGCAUUAUGCUGCUUAUUUUGAUGUCCCUGAACUUAUAAGAGUGAUUUUGAAAACAUCGAAACCAAAAGAUGUGGAUGCCACUUGCAGUGAUUUUAAUUUUGGAACAGCUUUGCAUAUUGCAGCAUACAACUUGUGUGCAGGUGCUGUGAAGUGCCUCUUGGAGCAGGGAGCAAAUCCUGCAUUUAGGAAUGACAAAGGACAGAUCCCUGCUGAUGUUGUUCCAGACCCAGUAGAUAUGCCGUUAGAGAUGGCUGACGCCGCAGCCACUGCUAAGGAAAUCAAGCAGAUGCUUCUAGAUGCGGUGCCUCUGUCAUGUAACAUCUCAAAGGCCAUGCUCCCAAAUUAUGAUCAUGUCACUGGCAAGGCAAUGCUUACGUCACUUGGCCUGAAGUUGGGGGAUCGUGUUGUUAUUGCAGGACAGAAGGUUGGUACAUUAAGAUUUUGUGGAACAACUGAAUUUGCAAGUGGGCAGUGGGCUGGCAUUGAACUGGAUGAACCAGAAGGAAAAAAUAAUGGAAGUGUUGGAAAAGUCCAGUACUUUAAAUGUGCCCCCAAGUAUGGUAUUUUUGCACCUCUUUCAAAGAUAAGUAAAGCAAAAGGUCGAAGGAAGAAUAUAACACACACUCCUUCUACAAAAGCUGCUGUACCUCUCAUCAGGUCCCAGAAAAUUGACGUAGCUCAUGUGACGUCAAAAGUAAAUACUGGAUUAAUGACAUCAAAAAAAGAUAGUGCUUCUGAGUCAACACUUUCAUUGCCUCCUGGUGAAGAACUUAAAACUGUGACAGAGAAAGAUGUUGCCCUGCUUGGAUCUGUCAGCAGCUGCUCCUCUACAUCUUCUUUGGAACACAGACAGAGCUACCCCAAGAAACAGAAUGCAAUCAGCAGUAACAAGAAGACAAUGAGCAAAAGCCCUUCCCUUUCAUCCAGAGCCAGUGCUGGUUUGAAUUCCUCAGCAACAUCUACAGCAAAUAAUAGCCGUUGCGAGGGGGAACUCCGCCUCGGAGAGAGAGUGUUAGUGGUAGGACAGAGACUGGGCACCAUUAGGUUCUUUGGGACAACAAACUUCGCUCCAGGAUAUUGGUAUGGUAUAGAGCUUGAAAAACCCCAUGGCAAGAAUGAUGGUUCAGUUGGAGGUGUGCAGUAUUUUAGCUGUUCUCCAAGAUAUGGAAUAUUUGCUCCCCCAUCCAGGGUGCAAAGAGUAACAGAUUCCCUGGAUACCCUUUCAGAAAUUUCUUCAAAUAAACAGAACCAUUCUUAUCCUGGUUUUAGGAGAAGUUUUAGCACAACUUCUGCUUCUUCCCAAAAGGAGAUUAACAGAAGAAAUGCUUUUUCCAAAUCGAAAGCUGCUUUGCGUCGCAGUUGGAGCAGCACCCCCACCGCAGGUGGCAUUGAAGGGAGCGUGAAGCUGCACGAGGGGUCUCAGGUCCUGCUCACGAGCUCCAAUGAGAUGGGUACUGUUAGGUAUGUGGGCCCCACUGACUUUGCUUCAGGUAUCUGGCUUGGACUUGAGCUCCGAAGCGCCAAGGGAAAAAAUGAUGGGUCAGUGGGUGACAAGCGCUAUUUCACCUGUAAGCCGAACCAUGGAGUCUUAGUUCGACCGAGCAGAGUGACCUAUCGGGGAAUUAAUGGGUCAAAACUUGUGGAUGAGAAUUGUUAAGCUUCUAAAAUAUUAAAUAAGCUCAAAUAUAUAUAUUUGGUGUAAAUAAAGAGUCCAUGGUAAAUGGUUUACUUUAUUUAGCCAUAUUAAAAUUUUGAAAAUAUAGUUAUCUUCUUAAAAACCAUUAUAACAAUUCAGAGAGAGUUCUUUACAAAGCCAUGAAUAUGAACUAUGGGGAAUCAUGGUUCUUUUAAAGCAAUUUUCAAAAUAAGUACCAAUUAAAGCUUUAGGUUCCAAGAAGAUUCUGGGACUCAGGAAGAAAAAGUGCCAUCAGGUGACCAGCUGUUGCAUUUCUUGCUUAUUCUGUUUUGUUUUUGCACAUCAUAAUGGAUUUUUCUUAGUGCCCUAAUUGUGAAGGGUUUCUCUAGCUUUGGUUAUGUGUAAUGUUCACGUGACCUUUUUUUGUCAAUCAUUUUUGGAAUUUUUCUUUCUUUCUGUGCUUUAUUACUAAUAAGUCCAAUGAGUGAGUAGUAGCUAGAUGACUAGUAUGUAGUUUUAUAUUUUGGUAAAAUUAUUUGCCCUUUCAGAAAUGCCUCAUCUAAAGAUACAUGAUAAUUUUGGAGUUGGAAGGGGCCUUAGAGGCUCUCCAGCUCUGCUUCUUGCCCAUUGCCAAAUACUGAAAUGGAAGCCCGUCUUACCUGGGGUCACUAACUGGUUGGUUAACUGAGCUAAGAAUAGACUGUGGGUCUCCUCACUUGUGGCCCAGUGCUCUUUCUGCUAUACAAAAUGUCUAAUCUCAGAUUUUUCUUCUGCUGCUUGACUGCUUCAUCUGGAUGAACUACAAAAAACCCAUGAUUAAGGUUUAUGAAUUCAAGUAAUAAUUAGAUUUUUUUUGCACAGACUUACUUAACUUCCUUAUUGGAUAUGUUUGUAACACAUAAACACAAAGCACUUUUCAAACAUGAUGCACUUUUAUCUUUGUGAAUAAUUUACUGUCCUUUCCUCCUGGGAUAUGAGAAACAUUUUAAAAAACGUAUUUAACAGAAGAGAGCAAAUAAAGAUAUAUCAGGAAGGAUGUAUUAGUUAUUUACUUAAAUGUUUAUAAUAUCUGGAUUUUUUUUGUUUUGUUACUCAUAGAACUGGUGUUGUUUGCUGUUUUUAUUUCUCUAAUUGUUGCAGAGUUCUGCCUGUUACAAAGCUACAGAACUGUAUUGUUUUUAUUUUCCUUCUUGAGCACAUGUUAACAAACUAAGCUUCACAUUAGAGUGAUGUCAUAAUGUAAAAUGUUUGCAUUGUGGUUAGGUAUUGAAGUUUAUGUCCUGUCUGUGUAAAGAUUCAUCUUUUAUUGUAAAUAUUUAGACUUUACCACAGAAAUAUUGGAACAGUUUGCUUUAUAAGAUUAAAAAGCAUCCUUCAGAAUGGAGCUUGCCUUGUGCUUAGAAAUAAUAUGUUGAACUAUUUUGCAAUAUACUAUUUUAAAUCUAAAUUCUGUCACUUCGCUGCCUUUUUAAAAUAGUGUGGUAUUUCAAAUAUUGCUAGAGCUAUUUUCCUGAAAUACAUUUGCAAAAUAAGGCUGCUUUGUAAUCAAGGAAUAUUUUUAUUGAUUGAAGGAAAUGACUGUACUGCGAUUCAAAAGUAAACUUAUUUUAUUAUACAGAUUAUUUCUUAAAAACUCUAUUUAUACCUUAACAUGAAAUCCAUGACCACACCAAACUUGGUUAUUCAUAAUUUUUCCUGUUAAAUAUAAAACACUGUAAGUUAAAAACAGUAAUGCCAACAUUGAAUUUAUUUUUGAGGUCAAAGAACCAGUUGUUCUCUUUAUAUUUAGAUGAGGAUGAUUGAGUCCAUAUACUAUGUAUGUUUACAUAUACUAUACAUGCACAUUAGGUGUUUUCAUUUGUGUUUUGCUUAUGAAAUGUCAUUUAAAGUUCACUUCUUGAGCAUCAAUAAAAAGGGAAGCUGUGUGGUUUUGGAA